GGGCGCCGGUGCUGUUGCCUUCAGGUGACCACGGAUUCGCCAUCGUGAGUUCCAGGUGGGCGCGCGGGGCCCACGUAGGGCAGGAGGCCAGCCCCGGGGGGAUCGGGCCCGGGACUCUGCGGAAUCUGGAGGCCGAAGCCCGCGCGCACGCAGGGUCUCUGCUGCUUCCCCAACGCCUGUUGCGUGGCCGCAGGACCCGCCGCCCUCCCGGUUGGGCCGCCCAGUCCCGGGCCGGGCGCGUGCACCCAGAGCUUCCGCGUUUCUAGUCCGGCUCCUCUGCUGGAUUGCAGCGCCGGCUGGGCACCAGGAGUACAAAGCGAAAACCCCCGCCGGCCCUUCUGUUCUCCACGGUCUCCAAGGAGACACGGACAACAGAACAACACUUCCGUGUGCUAAAUAGUAAAGCACCAAGGUACUCGAUCCAGGGGCGGCGUGCAGUGGGGAGGUGAGCUUUGGGUCGGCCGUCGCCCCUCGGCUACCGGCGGGAUCCAGAAACCGGGAGUCACCACCAAUACCGUUCUCAACUUUACUUCCAGCUGGUCACUACUGUGUCGGGAGAUUCUACCUUCUUUUCCGACUAACAUGUAUUUUUCUCCAGUCCUUUCUGCGGCGUCUCUAGUGCAGGCCACCGUCAUUUCUAACCUGGACGACUCCAGGAGCGUCUUUGCUGCUCGGGGACUCUUCCUUUGCCCAGAUCCACAAAGAUCUAUAACGUCUUUCUAAUCACGACACCUCUGCUUUAGAUGUUAAAGUUGCUUCACACUGGAACGCUUGCAAAGACAGGGUCAGAUGUGUUACUGGGCUGGAGUGUGGUGGCACAAUCACGCUCACUGCAUCCUUGACCUCCUGGGCUCAAGUGAUCUUCCCACCUCAGCCUCCCAAGUAGCUGGGACUACAGGAUUUUCAAAAUGGCUGCAGCUCCUCAAGCACCGGGGCGGGGAUCUCUCCGUAAGACGAGACCUCUGGUUGUGAAGACGUCGUUGAACAACCCAUACAUCAUCCGCUGGAGCGCUCUGGAGAGCGAGGAUAUGCACUUCAUCCUACAGACGCUUGAGGACAGGCUUAAAGCUAUUGGACUUCAGAAGAUUGAAGAUAAGAAGAAAAAGAACAAAACACCUUUUCUGAAAAAAGAAAGCAGAGAGAAAUGCAGCAUUGCUGUUGAUAUUAGUGAGAAUCUGAAGGAGAAGAAAACAGAUGCUAAGCAGCAAGUGUCAGGGUGGACGCCUGCACACGUCAGGAAGCAGCUUGCCAUUGGCGUUAACGAAGUUACCAGAGCCCUGGAAAGGAGGGAACUGCUGUUAGUUCUGGUGUGUAAAUCAGUCAAGCCUGCCAUGAUCACCUCACACUUGAUUCAGUUAAGCCUAAGCAGAAGUGUCCCUGCCUGUCAGGUCCCCCGGCUCAGUGAGAGAAUCGCCCCCGUCAUUGGCUUAAAAUGUGUUCUAGCCUUGGCGUUCAAAAAGAACACCACUGACUUUGUGGACGAAGUAAGAGCCAUCAUCCCCAGAGUCCCCAGUUUAAGUGUACCAUGGCUUCAAGACAGAAUUGAAGAUUCUGGGGAAAAUUUAGAGACUGAACCUCUGGAAAGCCAAGACAGAGAGCUUUUGGACACUUCAUUUGAAGAUCUGUCAAAACCUAAGAGAAAGCUUGCUGACGGUCGGCAGGCUUCUGUAACAUUACAACCCCUUAAAAUAAAGAAACUGAUUCCAAACCCUAAUAAGAUAAGGAAACCACCCAAAAGUAAAAAAGCUACUCCAAAGUAAUCUUGCAUAAACUUGUCAUGUCAUACAGUUUGUGAAAGGACACCUUGUAAAGAAGCCUUGAAACUAAUAAAAUGAGUUAUACUUACAUAGA